GACUCCCGCGCGCGCUCGGCUGGUCCCAGUCCCCGGGAGAAGAAGCGGAGGAGGGAGAGAGCCAGCGAGGCGGCCCAGGGGAGCGGGCGCGAGUGGCGGCUGCCGGAGCCGCCUGUGCACGGGCGGCGGCGAGGCGAGGGUGGCGGUCGCCUGAGCAGCUAGAGCCGGGGCGGCGCGGAAUCCGCAUCCGCCGCGAGUGUGAUGAAGCUACCCUGCCUCGCUGCUCCGCUUGCCGCCAGCUGACACCGCCUGCACCCAGCCCGCCCGGGAGGGGAGACGCCGCGGGGCCGUGACCUUGGCGGAGGAGGGCACACUGAUAAUUCUUGUAUCUUGAGAGUGGACCAAGUUUUGGGUGACAUGGCCCAGGGGAAUAAUUAUGGGCAGACCAGCAACGGGGUGGCCGAUGAAUCACCCAACAUGCUGGUGUACAGAAAGCCUCCUAUUCUCACUCCUUUGGGAUCCCAUGAACUGAGAGGGGAUGAGACUAUACAAAGAAAACACUGCCACUCAUAGCUACGCACCUAAAUUCAGCCCGAAGCAGAGGUGACUGCUGCCACAUCUCUAGGUGCUGAGAUGAAAGUAUGGAAGACGUCAUAGCACGGAUGCAAGAUGAAAAAAAUGGAAUUCCUAUUCGUACGGUCAAAAGCUUUCUUUCCAAGAUACCUAGCGUCUUCUCUGGUUCAGACAUUGUUCAAUGGUUGAUAAAGAACUUAACUAUAGAAGAUCCAGUGGAGGCGCUCCAUUUGGGAACAUUAAUGGCUGCCCACGGCUACUUCUUUCCAAUCUCAGAUCAUGUCCUCACACUCAAGGAUGAUGGCACCUUUUACCGGUUUCAAACCCCCUAUUUUUGGCCAUCAAAUUGUUGGGAGCCGGAAAACACAGAUUAUGCCGUUUACCUCUGCAAGAGAACAAUGCAAAACAAGGCACGACUGGAGCUCGCAGACUAUGAGGCUGAGAGCCUGGCCAGGCUGCAGAGAGCAUUUGCCCGGAAGUGGGAGUUCAUUUUCAUGCAAGCAGAAGCACAAGCAAAAGUGGACAAGAAGAGAGACAAGAUUGAAAGGAAGAUCCUUGACAGCCAAGAGAGAGCGUUCUGGGACGUGCACAGGCCCGUGCCUGGAUGUGUAAAUACAACUGAAGUGGACAUUAAGAAGUCAUCCAGAAUGAGAAACCCCCACAAAACACGGAAGUCUGUCUAUGGUUUACAAAAUGAUAUUAGAAGUCACAGUCCUACCCACACACCCACACCAGAAACUAAACCUCCAACAGAAGAUGAGUUACAACAACAGAUAAAAUAUUGGCAAAUACAGUUAGAUAGACAUCGGUUAAAAAUGUCAAAAGUCGCUGACAGUCUACUAAGUUACACGGAACAGUAUUUAGAAUACGACCCGUUUCUUUUGCCACCUGACCCUUCUAACCCAUGGCUGUCCGAUGACACCACUUUCUGGGAACUUGAGGCAAGCAAAGAACCGAGCCAGCAGAGGGUAAAACGAUGGGGUUUUGGCAUGGACGAGGCAUUGAAAGACCCAGUUGGGAGAGAACAGUUCCUUAAAUUUCUAGAGUCAGAAUUCAGCUCGGAAAAUUUAAGAUUCUGGCUGGCAGUGGAGGACCUGAAAAAGAGGCCUAUUAAAGAAGUACCCUCAAGAGUUCAGGAAAUAUGGCAAGAGUUUCUGGCUCCCGGAGCCCCCAGUGCUAUUAACUUGGAUUCCAAGAGUUAUGACAAAACCACACAGAACGUGAAGGAACCUGGACGAUACACAUUUGAAGAUGCUCAGGAGCACAUUUACAAACUGAUGAAAAGUGAUUCAUACCCACGUUUUAUAAGAUCCAGUGCCUAUCAGGAGCUUCUACAGGCAAAGAAAAAGGGCAGAAACAUCCCUAUUUUCCCAUGCCAUAAAAACUGUACACCAACACUGAGGGCCAGCACUAACCUGUUAUGAAAAGAGGGGAAAUCUCUCACGUCCAAGAGGUUAACAAGCCUUGCUCAGUCUUACUAAACGGAUCAUCUUGUAGCAUGAAUGCAGACUGGAGUCACUGCACACACUUUGUAGCUCAAUGUUGUGACCUGGAGCAGAGGACAUUAGAACAAGAUGUUGCAUGAGCAAAGGACCUAAAUUGUUAUUUUUGUGUGUACAUUCCAUCUCCAAUGGACUCUUCCGUCUCAAUGCCUCCAUUCCAAACUGUUGUCUGCUUUCUUUCUCCUUCUACUAUGCUGGAUCUGUGUCUCUUCCUUUUUAACAAGUUCAAGUGAAGUAAAACCUUUUCUUUUUUUCCUUCUUUCUCUCUCUCUCUCUCUCAAAGCUUCAGUUAGACACACAGUUCACUGAAAAUUCAGUCAGUCAAAAACUGGAAGAACUGUAAAAGAAAAAAGUAUAUAUCAAUAAGUAUACAUGUGGCUUCACAUUUAUUAAACAAUAAAUUCCGCACAGAAAGUUUCAUUUCACCAAUGUGUCACAGUCAGAAACAAACUCAUGUCUUCGUCUGUUGUCUGUACAUUCUCCGUUAAUGUUUCUCGCAUUUAUUUUUAUACCAUAUUUAAAGAAGAAACACCUUUUACUCCAAAUGUAUUAAAGUUGAUCCCUUCUCUGUAAAUUUGUGUAUGUUUAUAUUGUUGUUUUAUCUUUCAUUAAAAGAUGCAGAAUCUCAUUGCUUUUGUAACUUUUGACUUCCAUGCUAACUAAAAAGGAAAAUGCUGAGAAAUCCACAACCCACUACCGCAGAGUUAAAUUUAGGUUGUCACCUUGAAAUUUAUUUCAAGGUUUCAAGACAAGCUUGGAUAGUACGGAAGCCAGGGGCAGAUGGAAAUAUUUUUUGGAGGCUUACCUGAGACUUAGUAAUCCUUUUUCUCCCAUGGAAGAACAACACAAAUUGAUGUUCCACAUUUUCAAAGCUAUUUAAAAGGCCUUUCUGCCUCAUGAUGAAUAUGCAUCUGUAUAUUUUGCAAAUUAAUAUUUCUGUUUGAAUUAAGCUUGAGUGUGACUUAUUAAAUCAGGUACUGAUUUGUUCUUUAAAACACAAUUCUAAAAAUAUCAUAGCUCAGUGUCUCUUAACUUUUUGGAGGUUACAGAUUAUUUUGAGAAUACAGUCACCUCUUGGCAUCCCUGGGAAAUAAUUGGUUCCUGGACCUCCUCAGAUACCAAAAUCCACAGAUGCUCAAGUCACUAAUAUAAAAUGGUGUAGUGUUUGCAUAUAAACUACGUAAAUCCUCCCACAUACUAAGUCAUCUCUAGAUUAUUGUAAUAUCUGAUACAAUGUAAAUGCUAUUAGUUGUUAUACCGUAUUUUUAAUUAAUACAACUUUAAUUGUUGCAUUAUUAUUUUUAUUGUUGGAAGGUUGCUUGAAUCUAAAGCUAUGGAACCUGUGGACGAGGAGGGCCGACUGUGUGAUGUAAUUAGUAAAAUUUAGUGACGCUUACUAA